AAUGAGACAGCAUGGCCCGUACUAAGCAGACUGCCCGCAAGUCGACCGGCGGCAAGGCCCCGAGGAAGCAGCUGGCUACCAAAGCGGCCCGCAAGAGCGCGCCGGCCACGGGCGGGGUGAAGAAGCCGCACCGCUACCGGCCCGGCACCGUGGCUCUGCGGGAGAUCCGGCGCUAUCAGAAGUCUACGGAGCUGCUGAUCCGCAAGCUGCCCUUCCAGCGGCUGGUACGCGAGAUCGCGCAGGAGUUUAAGACGGACCUGCGCUUCCAGAGCUCGGCCGUGAUGGCGCUGCAGGAGGCCAGAGAGGCCUACCUGGUGGGGCUGUUCGAAGACACGAACCUGUGCGCCAUCCAUGCCAAGCGCGUGACCAUCAUGCCCAAGGACAUCCAGUUGGUCAGCCGCAUCCGCGGGGAGCGGGCCUAAGCGAAAUCCGCUCCUGCUCCCAAGAAGGGCUCCAAAAAGGCUGUUACGAAAGUGCAGAAGAAGGACGGCGAGAAGCGCAAGCGCAGCCGCAAGGAGAGCUACUCCGUUUACGUGUAGGAGGUGCUGAAGCAGGUCCACCCCGACACCGGCAUCUCGUCCAAGACCAUGGGCAUCAUGAACUCCUUCGUCAACGACAUCUUCGAGCGCAUCGCGGGAGAGGCGUCCCGCCUGGCGCACUACAACAAGCGCUCCACCAUCACGUCCCGCGAGAUCCAGACGGCCGUGCGCCUGCUGCUGCCCGGCGAGCUGGCCAAGCACGCCGUGUCCGAGGGCACCAAGGCGGUCACCAAGUACACCAGCUCGAAGUAAGAGUGUGCAAGGGACGCAAUAGAUCAACCACCUAACCCCAAAGGCUCUUUUCAGAGCCACUUCAGUAAUCGAGAAAGCAGCUGUAAACACUUGUCAGAGCGUUUGAUAGCUUUUGGUCAGGUAGGGAGUGUUACCAUGGUCACGGAUGCAUUCGGGUUUAGGACUAAGGAGUUUCCUGUAGUCCUGUAAUGAGUUGGCCCUCAGUCAUCCCCGUCUAGUCUUACUGAGUUGCUUGUUAUCUGUGCUACGAGAUUAGAAAGGUUUGACUCGUUCUGGGAUAUUUGGGAGGGAUGGAGGGAAGGAGGCGGGGGGUGGUUCUACACCCCUUCAGCCUUUAACCUGUAUCUUUAAAGUCGUUUUCCUUUUUGUUUCUGAAAGUAAUGAACGAGAUGAGAUUUCCCAUACAGAUGAGAAACCCUCGGUCCAACCUCUUACUAUUUCUUAGUGUUUUAAUCUGUUUUCCUUACCAUAUACCUACAGGCGUCUGUCACAAACUUUGUCUAAUAUAGCCAUGUGCUUUCGUCCCUUAGCCUUUUUGCAAGUCCUGACUUAGCCAUCCUCCCCUAACUUCCAUUCCAGUGACUUCAAACAGGGAGAUAUAUUGCCACCACCCCACCCCCUGUGGAGUAUUUGGCAAUAUCUGUAGAUGUUUUGGGUUGUCAGGUGUGUGUGUGUUGGGGGGGAGGUGCUAGAAGUAUCCAAUGGGCAGAGGCCAGGAGUGCUAAGCAUAAGGCACAGGACAGUCCUCUGGGGGGACAAAGAGCUACCUGGCCUGUAAUGUCUAUCUUUGGUGAUUGAGAGACCCCAGCGCCCAAAGACAUCCCUAACCUUCAGGAUUUAAUCCUCUUCAGUCAAACUUUUCCUUAACCCUAUCAGCCCAUGUUUUUCUUGGUGAAAGCUGAGCACUUCAUAGGCUGUUUACAGGUCCUUCUCCACAGGAAAAUACUUCCUCCAGGACAAGAACCCUGUCUUGGUUCCAAACUUUCCCAAUUAUAAGAGUCACCUUUGCGCUUGUUUUUUUUUUUUUUUUUGAGACGGAGUCUCGCUCUGUCGCCCAGGCCGGAGUGCACUGGCGGGAUCUCGGCUCACUGCAAGCUCCGCCUCCCGGGUUCACGCCAUUCUCCUGCCUCAGCCUCCCAAGUAGCUGGGACUACAGGCGUCCGCCACUACGCCCGGCUAAUUUUUUGUAUUUUUAGUAGAGACGGGGUUUCACCGUUUUAGCCGGGAUGGUCUCGAUCUCCUGACCUCGUGAUCCGCCCGCCUCGGCCUCCCAAAGUGCUGGGAUUACAGGCGUGAGCCACCGCGCCCGGCCUUGCGCUUGUUAAACCUGCUUCCAGGUGCUUCUCUUGAGGUUUCCUGAUUCAGCGAGACUGGAGGUGGGACCUGACGAGGUGGUUGGUUUUUAGUGUUCUCAGGAGUGUGGAUGUUUUAAUAGGUGUUGGGUCCUCAUGUUAAUCGACCUGUGGGUGUGUCACAGUCUUUGUGUCACAGAUGUUCUGAGAAAGGAAACAAUUUGAGGAUGAGUGGAGGGGAAUUUGUGGUGUAGAGAAGGCCACAGUUAAUAUGUGGGGUGAAUUUCUGAAGACCUCUCAGUUCAAAACUUGAAUAACUCAAGACUCAUCCUGACAAAAGCCAGUGGAUGUUUCUUUUGCCAAAUAAAAUAUACCCUUGGUGCAACUGGAAAAUCUUAGCUUAUAAUUAACUUGACAGCCUUUGAAAUUAAGCCAUUCUUGAUAAAUCUUGGGGGAAUUAACAACUUUGUGCUUAAAAUGAAUUUUACUAAUUUUUAUGAUGUUGAAGUUCAAAUUUACACCCAAUUAAAAGAUAUAAAAUGUGG